GUCCCGGGCCGCUCGUCCCGUCGGCUGCGGCCGCGCGCGGCCCGGGGUCGCCGUGAGUACUCGCCAGGCUGGCCUGUGUGGCCGCCACCACGGGCACAGGGCGGUGCGGCCGGGCCACGGGAAGGGUGCGGGGCUCGCCCCGUCUCCGCAGGGGUGGACGAAGUGAGAGGCUUGGACCGGGAGGUUCUGAGGGCCCCUCCUAGGCUGGACAGGCUUCACUCAGGCCCGGCGGCCGGGCGGCAUAGAUCGGGCCCAGAGCGUCUUUCCUGGGGAGCAACAGAAACCAAGCAGCAACAGCCCUUGGAAAGAGGCUAAAUUUUUCUUGACUUCUGCAGCAACAAAGACCGUGAAAAGUUGGCACUUCUGGCCUAACGCUGCCGUCAUCCUACCCCUCACCCCAGGGCAACCCAGGCUGGACAUUUAGUGCCUCCCUCUUUAUUCCUCUGUGAUCAUCCAGAUCAGCACUUGACUGUUUAUUUUCAAAUCUCACGAACCUCACCCCAAGAUCUUCACAUUCUGGAUCUCAGCUGCUCUUGAAGGACAGUGACUUGUUACCACCGCAACAGCAGAGCCUGCCAUCCCCAACAGAUCACCAGUUGUCCCUGACAUCGUGCCCUACCUUGUCUCCCUUUGUGGUCUCCUAAAUGCCCAUCUCGUUGGCCUUGGUUCGGCUAGUGGUAUGGAGGGGUGCUGCCUAGCACUGACCUGAGAGUGUGUGUGACCCACUGACCCAAUGGACAUCAAAGGCCAGUUCUGGAAUGAUGACGACUCGGAGGGAGAUAAUGAAUCAGAGGAAUUUCUCUAUGGCGUUCAGGGGAGCUGUGCAGCUGACCUGUAUCGACACCCACAGCUUGAUGCAGACAUUGAAGCCGUGAAGGAGAUCUACAGUGAGAACUCUGUAUCCAUCAGAGAAUAUGGAACUAUCGAUGACGUGGACAUUGACCUCCACAUCAACAUCAGCUUCCUCGAUGAGGAAGUCUCUACAGCCUGGAAGGUCCUCCGGACAGAACCUAUUGUGUUGAGGCUGCGAUUUUCUCUCUCCCAGUACCUAGAUGGACCAGAACCAUCCAUUGAGGUUUUCCAGCCAUCAAAUAAGGAAGGAUUUGGGCUGGGUCUUCAGUUGAAAAAGAUCCUGGGUAUGUUUACAUCCCAACAAUGGAAACAUCUGAGCAAUGAUUUCUUGAAGACCCAGCAGGAGAAGAGGCACAGUUGGUUCAAGGCAAGUGGUACCAUCAAGAAGUUCCGAGCUGGCCUCAGCAUCUUUUCACCCAUCCCCAAGUCUCCCAGUUUCCCUAUCAUACAGGACUCCAUGCUGAAAGGCAAACUAGGUGUACCAGAGCUUCGGGUUGGGCGCCUCAUGAACCGUUCCAUCUCCUGUACCAUGAAGAACCCCAAAGUGGAAGUGUUUGGCUACCCUCCCAGCCCCCAGGCAGGUCUCCUGUGCCCUCAGCACGUGGGCCUCCCUCCCCCAGCACGGACCUCUCCUUUGGUCAGUGGUCACUGCAAGAACAUUCCCACUCUGGAGUAUGGAUUCCUCGUUCAGAUCAUGAAGUAUGCAGAACAGAGGAUUCCAACAUUGAAUGAGUACUGUGUGGUGUGUGAUGAGCAGCAUGUCUUCCAAAAUGGAUCUAUGCUGAAGCCAGCUGUCUGUACUCGUGAACUAUGCGUUUUCUCCUUCUACACACUGGGCGUCAUGUCUGGAGCUGCAGAGGAGGUGGCCACUGGAGCAGAGGUGGUGGAUCUGCUGGUGGCCAUGUGUAGGGCAGCUUUAGAGUCCCCUAGAAAGAGCAUCAUCUUUGAGCCUUAUCCCUCUGUGGUGGACCCCACUGAUCCCAAGACUCUGGCCUUUAACCCUAAGAAGAAGAAUUAUGAGCGGCUUCAGAAAGCUCUGGAUAGUGUGAUGUCUAUUCGGGAGAUGACCCAGGGCUCAUAUUUGGAAAUCAAGAAACAGAUGGACAAGUUGGAUCCCCUGGCCCAUCCUCUCCUGCAGUGGAUCAUCUCUAGCAACAGGUCACACAUUGUCAAACUACCUCUCAGCAGGCAGCUGAAGUUCAUGCACACCUCACACCAGUUCCUCCUGCUGAGCAGCCCUCCUGCCAAGGAGGCUCGGUUCCGGACCGCCAAGAAGCUCUAUGGCAGCACCUUUGCCUUCCAUGGGUCCCACAUUGAGAACUGGCAUUCGAUCCUGCGCAAUGGGCUGGUCAAUGCAUCCUACACCAAACUGCAGCUGCAUGGAGCAGCCUAUGGCAAAGGCAUCUACCUGAGCCCCAUCUCCAGUAUUUCCUUUGGAUACUCAGGAAUGGGAAAAGGACAGCACAGGAUGCCCUCCAAGGAUGAGCUGGUCCAGAGAUACAACAGGAUGAAUACCAUCCCCCAGACCCGAUCCAUUCAGUCACGGUUCCUGCAGAGUCGGAAUCUAAACUGUAUAGCACUUUGUGAAGUGAUUACAUCUAAGGACCUCCAGAAGCAUGGGAACAUCUGGGUGUGCCCUGUGUCCGACCAUGUCUGCACAAGAUUCUUCUUUGUAUAUGAGGAUGGUCAGGUGGGCGAUGCCAACAUUAAUACUCAGGACCCCAAGAUACAGAAGGAAAUCAUGCGUGUGAUCGGAACUCAGGUUUACACAAACUGAGGGGGCCCCAGCCCUCGUACCACCCCUGUUACCCCAGGAUCCAUCUGCCCUCAUAAAAGUGUUCAGGUACAGCAGCUGAGGCUGCCCUGAGGAAUCAAGGGGCCAUUACCAAGGGGCAGGAAAAGGAUAUGUAAGAGGUGGCCUUCAUGGUAGAGCUUGACCCAAGAACUACUCCACAUUCGGAUGGCCCAGACUGACUCCAUCCCCUGACUUUCCCUUUGACUUCACCCUGUUUGUAAAUAAAACAAUAAAAUGGAAGGUGCUGUGGACUGGA